AUGGGUUGCUGUGGUUGUGGAGGUUGUGGUGGCUGUGGUGGCUGCGGUGGUGGCUGUGGUGGUGGCUGUGGCAGAUGCACCACCUGCAGGUGCUACCGGGUGGGCUGCUGCUCCAGCUGCUGCCCCUGCUGCCGUGGCUGCUGUGGAGGCUGCUGCAGCACUCCCGUGAUCUGCUGCUGCCGCCGCACCUGCAGCUCGUGUGGCUACAGCUGUGGGAAGGGCUGUUGCCAGCAGAAGUGCUGCUGCCAGAAGCAAUGCUGUUGCUAG